CCCACCCAAGGCCCCUCAGCUGGAAUGUGGUAGGACUGGUCUGGAGGGACUAUGGCCCUUCUGGCCCACUUGGCACCAUGCUGAUCUCAGGAUUUUAGGGGCCUGCUCCAUGGUACCUUGGCCAGAGAGACCAUGAAUGAUGGAAUGAGGAUGCCCCACCUCUGCCCCACUGUUUCCACUGUCUUCCCUGUUUUGGGGAUCUCCUCAUGCCUAGCCUCAUGCUUCUGCCUGAGGCAUUUUUCACUGUUAGUCUUUUUGAAUAAAACUUUGUUGGGAUUGAUAGUAGUUCCUCCACUCACCAGCCUAACGCAUGUUUAGCUCCUCGAAACCCCGAGGGUGCCCGCUGAGGCAAGGUGGAGGGGAAGCUUUCAGGUUAUACCCAGCUUCAGAUUAAAUCCAGCCCAGGGGAGAUAAAAUCCUGGUUCUUUUGCUCGUCACUUCUGUGAUCUCUGGCAAGCUGCUUAGCCUCUCAGAGCCUUGGUUUCCCUUCGUUUGCGAAAUAGGAAACUCAUAAAAGUGAGUCUCCAUGCAUUCUACAUAAAAGUGAGUGGAAAGAACACAACUUAGGAAUUAAUAAAGCAUCAAUACCUGGGAGCACACUGUGUGCUUAAAUCUUAGUUUUUUCACCUUUCCCUGUUGCCAAGAAUGUACUCAAGAGGUUGCUUUUGAGAGUCAUCCAGGGAUUGGUUGUAGUUUUUCUUUCCUGGAUCCAACUUCCUUUAUUGUCGCAGGUUGUGAAUAUCUCUUUGAAACACUGUGGACAAUCUGUGGGGCUUAUGGUAACCUGUCUCCAUGGUGACGCAGCUGCCCUGUGUCCUCUCAGGAUUUGCUUGUAGAUCCUGCUGUUGCAUUGACCCUGGAAGUUAAGCCAAACCCAGCAUGAUAAGGAGUGUGAAUGCCUCCUGCUUCUAAUUCCUGCAGCAAGGCCUGUUGGGUUAUUCUUACCCAGCCAGAGAGAAAGAUCCAUCUUGAGAACAUCAGAGUGGCAUUCUUUCUUGAGUCAGUACUCCAGUACUUCAAAUCCACAGAACAUGUUCAAUUUCGGUGCAAAGAGAAGAAAUAUGAUUAUGAUAAUUUGCCCAGGACAUCUGUUAUCAUAGCAUUUUAUAAUGAAGCCUGGUCAACUCUCCUUCGGACAGUUUACAGUGUCCUUGAGACAUCCCCGGAUAUCCUGCUAGAAGAAGUGAUCCUUGUAGAUGACUACAGUGAUAGAGAGCACCUGAAGGAGCGCUUGGCCAAUGAGCUUUCGGGACUGCCCAAGGUGCGCCUGAUCCGCGCCAACAAGAGAGAGGGCCUGGUGCGAGCCCGGCUGCUGGGGGCGUCUGCGGCGAGGGGCGAUGUUCUGACCUUCCUGGACUGUCACUGUGAGUGCCACGAAGGGUGGCUGGAGCCGCUGCUGCAGAGGAUCCAUGAAGAGGAGUCGGCAGUGGUGUGCCCGGUGAUUGAUGUGAUCGACUGGAACACCUUCGAAUACCUGGGGAACUCCGGGGAGCCCCAGAUCGGCGGUUUCGACUGGAGGCUGGUGUUCACGUGGCACACAGUUCCUGAGAGGGAGAGGAUACGGAUGCAAUCCCCCGUCGAUGUCAUCAGGUCUCCAACAAUGGCUGGUGGGCUGUUUGCUGUGAGUAAGAAAUAUUUUGAAUAUCUGGGGUCUUAUGAUACAGGAAUGGAAGUUUGGGGAGGAGAAAACCUCGAAUUUUCCUUUAGGAUCUGGCAGUGUGGUGGGGUUCUGGAAACACACCCAUGUUCCCAUGUUGGCCAUGUUUUCCCCAAGCAAGCUCCCUACUCCCGCAACAAGGCUCUGGCCAACAGUGUUCGUGCAGCUGAAGUAUGGAUGGAUGAAUUUAAAGAGCUCUACUACCAUCGCAACCCCCGUGCCCGCUUGGAACCUUUUGGGGAUGUGACAGAGAGGAAGCAGCUCCGGGACAAGCUCCAGUGUAAAGACUUCAAGUGGUUCUUGGAGACUGUGUAUCCAGAACUGCAUGUGCCUGAGGACAGGCCUGGCUUCUUCGGGAUGCUCCAGAACAAAGGACUAACAGACUACUGCUUUGACUAUAACCCUCCCGAUGAAAACCAGAUUGUGGGACACCAGGUCAUUCUGUACCUCUGUCAUGGGAUGGGCCAGAAUCAGUUUUUCGAGUACACGUCCCAGAAAGAAAUACGCUAUAACACCCACCAGCCUGAGGGCUGCAUUGCUGUGGAAGCAGGAAUGGAUACCCUUAUCAUGCAUCUCUGCGAAGAAACUGCCCCAGAGAAUCAGAAGUUCAUCUUGCAGGAGGAUGGAUCUUUAUUUCACGAACAGUCCAAGAAAUGUGUCCAGGCUGCGAGGAAGGAGUCGAGUGACAGUUUCGUUCCACUCUUACGAGACUGCACCAACUCGGAUCAUCAGAAAUGGUUCUUCAAAGAGCGCAUGUUAUGAAGCCUCGUGUAUCAAGGAGCCCAUCGAAGGAGACUGUGGAGCCAGGACUCUGCCCAACAAAGACUUAGCUAAGCAGUGACCAGAACCCACCAAAAACUAGGCUGCAUUGCUUUGAAGAGGCAAUCAUUUUGCCAUUUGUGAAAGUUGUGUUGGAUUUAGUAAAAAUGUGAAUAAGCUUUGUACUUAUUUUGAGAACUUUUUAAAUGUUCCAAAAUACCCUAUUUUCAAAGGGUAAUCGUAAGAUGUUAACCCUUGGUAUUUAGAAAAUUAAAACCUUAUAAUAUUUUUCUAUCAAGAUGUAUAUUUUACAGUCGUGCCUUUUACUCUCAUUAGCAAAAAAGAUAAAGAUUUUAUUUUGGUAUUUACAAGAAUUCCCAGGUACGAAGAUAUCUGCAUGGGUGGAAAUCAGGUUCAAGCAACGUACUUUGCAUUAACUGAUAAUACCUCAGCUGCGGGGUUAAAGUUUUCCCAGUAUAGAGAGACUGUCACUAGGAACAUUGUAUUGAUUUAUUCAGGUCAUUGAGAUCUUCUAGAUGUAUUUUAAAAAGAAUGCUUUUUGGUUAUGUGUUGCUACCACAGUUAACACUCCAUAAUGUUCAUGUCAGCCAAAGAGGACUAACCAAAGCUGAAAUCUCAGAGAACAAUUUGCUUUACUAAGCUGAGUCAACUUGAGAGCGAACUUCUAACAAUGCCGCACUGUAGUGUGGCUGGUUCUACCACUAUGACUUUAAAACAUGUUUAUAUCAUUUUUAAUUUUUAUGAUACGGUAGUGUCAGGGAGAAAUGUAAUGUUCUAUAUGAAAUUCCUUUUUCAAGUUUGUUCAUUAAUAACAGUUAUUAAUUUAAAUCAGCGUUAGAGUUUGUGCUGCUGCAACUGCUGUGAAAAUUUCUCUGAGUAAUUCUGAUUUGUGAAUGAUCCCAGACCAACCCUGAGAUUUUGUCAACCUGAUUAAGUCAAUAUGAAUGAUUAAAAAGAUGUGAGAACACUGA